CACUCCAGUGUGGGCGACAGGGUGAGACUUUGACUCAAAAACAAACAACAAACAAACAAACAAACAACAGAGACCCUAAUCCCAGCCAUUCAGAGAGUCAGGGAUGAGGACAUGUCUGGGCCAGUUUUCUCUGAGACUUGGUAUUUGCUCUCUGGGAGAGAGAGGAUCUCUUUGUUUUGGAUUAUGAACCAACCAAAGUAGACUUGGGGCUUCCAUACUUUUGUUCUGAUGGGAGAAUGAAGGCACUGUGGUGGACAGCAGAAUCCAGAGAGAGAUGACAUACCUGCCCAUAUUCCCGGACUUUCUGGAUCCAGCCAUGCCUGACUUGGACAAUUCAGUAAGUAUUCUUCCUUGCUCAUGAAGAUUCAAGUUGGGUUUCUGACUCUUGCAGUUGGAUAAUGAGGCUCAGAGUGGCAGGGAGUGGAGGGUCCUUUUCAAGGGAUGCUCUUCUACUCCACCACACAGUUCAGAUGGUGCCAGCCUUGGGGUGGGCUGUGGACCAGGCAGCCACUGGCAGUGGAAGAGAGACAGGCAGCCCCAGGCCCCCAGGAGUCAUGCUGGUGAGAUGGUCAGUGGUGGCAUGGCUGAGGUGGGGACGGCAGGGCCUGAGGACCUGCAACCUUGGAUUUCUUGGAGACAUGUUGGGCUGGCACAACUGGGCUGCCACCCUGGGGGUAAAGAUCUGCCCAGCCCCCAAGCCCAGAGAUACCCGGCCUGAUCUAGGCAACCAGUCCUGGGCUCCAGAGAGUUCCUCUGGCCCCGAGGACGUGCAAUGUGGGGUGAAGCAAAGCAGAGACCAGGACAGAAGAUUCACUUCCUCAGACGAUGAAGCUUACUGUCUCUCCACCGCUCAUGCCAAGAGCCUGGACAUGCAGGUGGGCAUGGAUAGGAACAGCUGAGUGGGAGUGUCAGUGGCACUGGAGUAUGCAACACCAAGUGUGUACGUGCACAAGCUCUAAGUGAGAAGGGCACUAGUGUGUGUGCACCAAAGCUGUCUGAGCAAAUGUCCACGAAACCACAGGAGGUGGAGCUGAGGGAUGCUACAUGUGAGUGUGUGCCAGGGGUAUCUCUAGGAACUUGGGAGGGGCCCCAGUGUGUGUAUGUGCAUGUGGGCUUGGCCAGUGUGACAAUGGAUGUUCCUCGUGGUGGCUGUGAACAGCCUUACUCUGUAUCAACCCUCCUUCCGCCCUCUUCUGGGCGAUGCCUGUUGCUUGUGUGUGGCAGCAGCUGCUGGAGCCCUUUGCAGAGACCUGGGACCUCACCACACCCAUACACGGGGACCCAAUGAUGGCUCUUGUGGACUAUCACGAUGGCGUCAUCGCCAGCACGGUGACUCCCCUGAAGACUUUUUUCUGGCCAGAGGAGCCCAUUUGGCCUCCACAAGGGGCAGGAAUGAACAUUCUCCAAAGGGCAGCCUCCAAAAAUGUCUGCUGAGCAUCAGGGUACAAACAACCCGUCUCUCCCACCUGAGGGCGGGCGUCACUUUGAGGUGCGUUCUACUCUGUGUCUCAGAGUCACCAGUGGGACUGCGCUCAGUGGCCUGCAGUGGUGACCUGCUUGGUGACCCCCUCACUGGCUUCCUUGCCUUUCUUGUUUCCUGCCUCACUCCAUCUGGUACUCCUGGGAACACUUCCCUAACCAAACUCUCACCCACAUCCUCAUCCCAGGGUCUGGCCCUGGGGCCCCUGUCUCCAUCGUCCUGUGAUGCAGCUUCACCUUCCAUCUCCUUGGGCCUCUGAUGAGCCCAGGUACCUGGGGUGUUCUCCUUGGCCCCUGGCACAGACAGGCGGCAUCUCCUUAGGAAUGUGCAAAGGACCUUGAAUGUGGUGCCAUAUGUGACACACCACAGCAUAGGGCAUGUCGUGGAUGGAGGAGCAGGAAAAGCCAAGAGCGUGACAGUCCCAAAGGCCUGUGGGAUCCUAAGUCUUUGUGGUGGGAGCUGGGUGUCGGUGUGGGGUGGUUUCGGUUGGGGGCAGCACAUGGCUGGACACCAUCACUGUGGAAGUUUCUGCAUUCAUUCCCAGGAGGUGGAGCCCCAGAGCACUGAGGUGGCACCAGAGCCAUGCCUAGUGAUGUUCAGAACAGAGGGCAUGCAAAAUGAUUAUUUUGCUUACAGAGAGGGGGACAUAAGUGUCAGGCUUUGUCCAGAGAGUGAUGCUGGCGGGGCGGGGGUGAGCCCCAAAAAUGGAAUACUUGAAUGGGUUCAACCUCAUAGAACAUCUCAAGGGUGGAAGAAAAGCCCAGGGUUAAAAUGACGGGUUUUGUCUGCAAUUAUGAGUGCUGGUGGGUAUUGUGUUUCAAGGUGAGAGGAGGGGCUUCCUCAUUCUUCAGGGCCUGACUUGUUCACUUUGAGCAGUGGCAGCAGCGAGCCGGCAGGUGGCAGUGUGGGCUCAGGGUGGGGGUGAUAGGCGCAGCAGAGCCAGCCUUGGCCUGUCCAGCAGGGACGUGGGCUGGAGAACCAGAAGGAUGAGCCUAUCUCGUGGUCUUUCCCCCCGCUGCACCCUCCUUCAGGAUUGCACCCCACUUUCAAGGCACUUGGGGUCUAAGACUAUAUUAAUGGACUAUUCGAAUUUUGGAUUGCACCCCACUUUCAAGGCACUUGGGGGCAUCUAGGACUAUGUUAGUGGGCUCUAUUGGAGUUCUGGUGGGAGGGAAAUGUGACAGAGGAAGGGGCCCAGGCUCUGUCCGCUAAGAGAUCAAUAGCCCAAGCCAUGGUGUUGUGGAGGGCAUGGAAAGGAAGAGGGGAAUUCCUGCAGAGGGUGAGACAACAGCUCAUUUCAGUUUCAUUGCCACUUUCCUCUCUUUCCUGGUGGUACAAGCCAUCAGGGUGCUACAAGCCAACUCCUGUUAGAGUAAAACGUGUAGUCUCUGAAGUUCCUAGAGUCAGGUCCUGAAGUUGAUGGCCCAUCCUCAUGACGUUACACCAGCCAUGUCUCAGAGAAAUGAUGCCAAGUUUCAGUGAGGUUAAAAAAAAAAAAGCAACUCCUGUAAGGCACUGACUAUCCAAAUAUCCACAUCAACAGGAAAAUGACAAGGCUUCAAUGGUGCUUAAUCUUGAGAGGUAAUGAAUGGGUAGAGAUUGCUAGCCGGAGGUGUAUUUUCAUUUUGUUGCUAUUUAGUGUUUCCUUUUCUUACAAGUUUCAGAAGGUAUAAACCCUACUCGGGAGGCUGAGGUGAGAGGAUCGCUUGAGACCAGGAGUUUCAACUAGCCUGGGCAACAUAGUGAGACCCUGUGUUUACAAAAAUUCAAAAUCAAAAAUUAGCUGGGUAUGGUGGUGCAUGCCUGUAGUCCCAGCUGCUUAGGAGGCUGAGGUGGGAGGAUCACUUGAGCCCAGGAGUUCAAGGCUACAGUGAGCUAUGUUCAUACCAUUGCACUCCAGCGUAGGCGACUGAGUGAGACCCUGUCUGAAGAAAAAAAGAAAAGAAAAAAAGGAACCUUAUGCACUCUCUGAAAGUGUUACUUCUUGCUACAUUUUAUUGAUAUUAUGUAUUUAUUUUGAACACAGAAAAGAUACAUUGUUGCUUAUUCAUUGCCUAGUCCAGGAACAAGAAAAGCUAUUCAGCUCCAUCUUUCAAACACUGAUGAGUAGGUAGGAAUUUUUAUCCCUUUUUUUCCCCCAGCACUCUCUGGAAUUGCAGAAGCAGGAUGUGUUUCUUAAAAGAGUCUCAUUCCUGGACUGCAUUUUAAAGGCUAUACAGUACAACAGACAGAUAUUUUUUGCCUAGAAAACAGUACACCACUAAGGUGGUCAGAACUGCUUGUAAACAAGUCCCUCCCCCAGAUGGAGUCUGGGGCUCCAGGAGGCUGCACGCAGGAUGCUACAGAACUUCUGGGUGGAUUCCUUUCAGCUCCGCACCAGAAGAAAUGCUAUCUCUACAGAAAAUAAAAUUCAAGAUUGCCAUCCUUGCCACUCCUCUGCUUAAGAAAGAGAUUACUAAAUAGUCUUAGCCCUUCAUUGGAGGAACAGAAAUGUGGGGAAGCAGGAUAGGGUGCUGUUUUUUAACGACGAGGGACAAGAGGUGGGAGGGAGGCAGAGUGAUGGCCGCUGGCGAUGCUAGCAGGGACACUGCUCAGAGAUGCUUGGCUGCCACCCUCUGUGGGCUGGGUCUUCAGGAAUCACCUCUGUUACCUGCGUGGUCUUUGAUGGAAAUCGCUGGGGUUUCUUGGUCAAGAUCUGAGCCAGCCUUUCUGCAGCCAGGCUGACCCUACAAAUCCCCUUCUGUGGCAGCAAGGCUGAGUAGCCUUCUGGUCCUCUUGUGGUGGCAAGGUGGUAUUUAUGGGGAGCAUAUCCCCUUCAUUUUGUCUCUGCAAACACCCACGUGGGCAAGGCCAGAACACAGCCACUCACCAUCCCCAGCUAUGAGCAGCCACCUAGAAGGACAGCACCAGCUCCGGGGUCUGGCUCUGACCCAUUCGCGUGCAGGCCACAGUGGUCGGCCAGGCAGGGACUGAGGGAGGGGCCACUUCUCUGCCUCAGAGAGGUGCCCAGGCAGCACUGUGGUGAAGCCACCUGGAGAAGGGCAAUGGCCUCAUCUUCCUUGAAGACCCUUAGUCCUGGGCAGUGGCUGGACUGAUGAGGGAACCGCCGCUGCACACCCACGGAGGGCCCUGCCCAUCUACCUGGGGCCUGCAGCGUCAGAGAUAGCUCUACUAGCACCACCUGACUGAGGGACUGAGGGUACUGGGGUUGGGAGGGGGCCUAGUGGGCUGUGAGGGCCUCCAGUUUGCGCCUGAGACCCCAGACCCAGGUCCCCCACCUUGUAAGUGGCAGGGUGGUGAUGUUGUGGCUCAUCUGCCCUGGAAUCGAGAGAUAGGCACAGCGCACAACGGAACCUCACUGGGGCCUGUCCCGCCUCCCAGGAGGACAAGCUGGCCCUGGGGUAGGGGUCAGGGCAGGCAGCUGACCUUGGAUGGUCCAGCAGUUUCCAGAGGCAGAAUAGAAUUUGGGCGCAGCUUGCUGGGCGAGGGUAGGGGCAAACGGGCCCAGGAGAGGGAAGAGAAAAUCCCACUUCCUACUUCGCCUCUCUCUCCGAAGCGCUCUCUACAGAGGCACAACAAACAGGCCGGGAGGAGGGACGGGAGGCCAGGAGAGCUCCACGUUCCGUGAAACCUUUGCAGAGGGGGACCUCAGAACCCUGGGACCUGGAUUUGGGACCUGACUCAGCCCUCAUAUGCGGUGUGAGCUCAACGCAUGAACACUGAGCUGCCUGGGUCUGCGGUGCCUCGAAACAGCAGUGGCCACUGUCUAGGGAGCAUCUCCCCGCAGCGCACUGGGUGUGCAGAGGCUGGGUAGGACCAACCUCAGGCUACCAGACACCCUGGUCUCCAGCCACUCCAAAGUUCCCCUUCUCAGUUUAGGAAAGAGUCCCCUGGGCCCCUCUGAACCCACAGAUGCAGAGCAAAAGAGCACCCAUUGCCCCGAAAGGACUGGCAGCACCACCCCUGCUCGAGCCCCUGGGGCAGGGGUGAAGGUGGAAGGCCAAGGAGGAGGACACGGGCCAUUCAUCCAGGGCUGGAGGGGUCUCCUAGCAGGGAAUGGUGGAGGCCCUGACCCCUUUCCCUCUUCGAGUACUGAUGGGUGAUCUGCCUGAGGGGGGCUGGCAGGAGAGGAACAAAAGCCCUCCAGAGAAGAGCUCCCCAUGGGGAGGGGGCUGCUUGAGGGCCCUGAGGGCAGUUUGGACACAGCCACUCCUGUGGGCAUGAUCACAGGCACAGGGCCCUCCUGGCCACAAGCUCCACCUGUCCUUUCUCUUCCCACUGCCACUGUCUCUGGGGUCCUCAGGAGCUGAGGGCAUAACUCCCUCCUUCUGGCUCCAUGACCCCCCACUUCUCUGAGAGGAACCCGUCUUGAUCCCUAAGGCCAGUCUCUGCCUCAGUGGCUACAGGUGAGGCCACAGAGACCCCAGGCUCAGCCAGACCCUUGUUGCCUGGGAGGUCUCGGAAGGUGUGUGCGUGUAUGUGUUCGUGUGUGCAUGUAUGUGUGUGUGUGUGUUUGGAGGGGGAAUCACCUCUGUCUUCGUAGUCGUGCCCCCACCUUCCCCACCCCUCUCCACCCCUGCCUCAUGCCUACCCAGCCCUGUCCAGGCACUGGACCCAACCAGCCUUGGGGGUGCCUGACCACAAUGGAGGCCUGCAGCUGGGGCAUCCCCUCGUGCCUGAGGCCAACCCAACCCUCUGCUCUGACUCAGGGAGAAGUUGGCUCCCAGGCACCCCCAGGGCAUCUGUGCACCUCCACCUCCAUCAGAAGCAGCCCCACCUGUUCCUGUCCUUUAGAUGAGCUGCACCGGGCAGAGGCAGCUGGGGAUGGGGGAGGUGCCUGUGUCCUCAGGCUAUGGCCUCAGGAACCAAGGGCUCAGGUCUAACCCUGAGCCACAUCCCCAGAUACCCACAGUAUCUUCCUUCCCAGGAAAACCCAGGAAGCAGGGUUAUUUGUCCUUAUUUCAUAAACAAAGAAAUGGAGCCCCUGAGAGCCACAGUGACAUGCCUGAGAGCAUCAACCUGGGCGGCGUCCAGGAUGGGCUCAAACCCAGGGGGAAGUUGAUCCCACAGCCACGGAAAUAGCCAGAUACUCCUCUGGCCUUCCCUCCCACCCUGAGGGAGACACCCGGAGGAGCAGAUCCCCAGGGAAUUCAGAACAGCUGCCACGGAACCUCCCCUGAAACUGCAGGGGCAUUCCCGGCAUGCCUACUCAACAGCCUGAGGAGGGCACCAGCUGAGAGACAGAAUUUUUGGAAGAACUUAGGAAAGAAACUAAGAAAAGACAACAGCACACAGCAACAAGCAGUCAUCCGGGCCUCUCAUGUCACCGAGAACAUUAUGGUGGGCGCCUGUGAGCUCUUCCUGACCACCCAAGACUUCUAGGAUGCUUUCCCGACCACCCUGCUCCACCCAGGGCAGAGUUGCCAACUCCUUGAUGCCUCCUGUGUUGCAAUCCCAGUCAGAUGAGGUCCCAGGGCCCCAGGGUGGGCGGCGGCUCACCGUAGCCGUGCUCGUACUCUCGGUGUCGACGCCGGCGGUGGUGAUGAUGGUGGUGGUGGUGGCGGUGGUGGCGGUGGCGGUGCCGCUGAAGCCGGGCCUGCCUGUCCCUGCGGAUGCUGCCCACAAUGAUGGUGAUGCAGGAGAGGAUGAUGACCACACCUAUGACGGCACUCGCCACCAGCACGGGGGACACGAGCAGAUGGCUGUGCUCCGAGCUCUCUGAGAAUGUGGGGUAGAAGUAGCUGGUGCGGUUGUAUCGUGCUACUGUGGACAGAGAGAGAGGACACUGAGCUGGAGCCCAGGCCUGCCACACCCCUUCCUUCUCUGCCCGUGCUGCCCUGUGAGCUGUUGCUCCCUAAAUAAAUGGAGGAGGGUCUGGGCUCAGGCCCACGGACUCUAUCCUGGCUGCUCCUGGGGGAGAAGGAGAGCAGCACCUCACUCCGCUGCCUGCAGGAGCCUCUGGUAGUGAGGGCUGACUGUCCCUCCUCUCCUCUGAAGCCUCUGCCCACAAGCUGAACUACCUCACAGAUAGGAAACAGGAAGCUCAGAGAGGGCAGUGGACUUGCCCAAGGUUACCCAGCAAAUUAGUGGUAGAGCUGAGGCUUGAAUCCAAGACUCUUAGAGCUAGACAAGUUGAAAGGUCAACAUGAUUUUACCAAUGUCUUAGGAAGCAGUGGGGGAUGCACAGGGGGACAGAGUAUGAGUAACGAUUCUGCCGGCUUCAGGCAGGCCUGGGGCUGUGGGCUGAAAUUGACCCAGAUGCGUCAGGGGCUUGGAUCAGAUGAGAGAAGGUUUCCCAGAAGAGGUAAGGCCAAGGUGAUCUUGGAGGGUGAGGAUGAGUUAGCUCAGGGAAGGCAGGGAGAGGCAUUCCAGGAGGGACAAAGGCACAGAAGGGUAGAGGGGACUUCCAGGGAGGAUGUGGUGUGGUGGGAGCAAGGGGAGAGUGCAGGAACCUCCUCCAGGACUAACAGCUGGAUCCUUGAGAGUCCUACGGAAAGAAGCUCCUGGGGACGGGUGACUUAGUCCUCUCACCGGAAAAGAUGCUGGGGCCUUGGGAGCUGGGGUCCUGGGGAGGGGUCUGAGUCAGCUAGGGGCAGCCAUGGGCACCCACUGCCUCACGUGGACAGUCAGCUCCGCAUUAGUGAGUGUCUUGGAGUGUCACUGAAUUCCCUCCAACUCAGCCCUGCAACUUAGGAUGCAACUUUCUCCUUUCACAGAUGGGUGGACUGAGACUCAGCGCUGGUAAGUGACUGGCCCAUGGUUGCUCAGUUACUCCACGGCAGAGCUAAGCUAGAACCCAGAUCUGGCUUCAAAGUCCAGUGCUUGCUCUCUUGCCCUCAGUGCCUCUCCUGCUCUCAGUGCAAACCCUUCCUGAGGCUGCCAGCCGGAUCUCUGAACAGCAGUAGGGAGCCAGCUUCAGACAUUCAAUGAACCACAGGGUCACGGGCAAGCACCAGGAAGGUCAGAUCUUUCGUAGGCUCUGUUCUGAGAGGGGUCCCCUUGCACGUUCUCCCAGAGCCCAUGUUCAAGCCCCAGCUUUGCAUUUGUUACAUAUGAUCAUGUCUGGUUUCCAGGGCUUGUGUUUGAUCACUCUCUGUGUCCUCAAACUCAACAAUGGGGCUAGGCACUCCAAAGUUUCCUAAUGCAUGUAUUGAGUGAGUAGCUCCAGUCUUGAGACCAGAUGGGGAAAUGGCAGGGAGGCCUUGCGAUGCCUCAGGAGAGUGAGGCCUCUGUCUUGGGUGGUAAUCAAGGAGAGCGUGGGUGGCCACCUGCCUGAGUAGCUGUAGGAGGGCUUUUUUCCCAGGUGAGGGCCUGGCCAUCUACCAAUCAGAGGCUUGACACUCAGCUGUGAUCGUUUCUCCUUCCCAUACCUUUCUAGCACUGACCCCAAAAGCCUCAAUCACACUCAACCUAGGACAGGAACAGGUGGUAAAGCACAAACUCGGGACCUUAGCUGGGGCUAGAAACAUGCCCUUGGGGCAGGUGUGGCCCAUGCUGGUGGCUCUUGCAGCCUACUAGCCUUCAUCAGGAGGGAGUGAGAUGGAGGCUCUAGUGUCUGGGCCAGUGUGUCAUCUCACUCUUGAGAGCCAAGCCUUUGCUGAAGUUCACUGUAAGACGCUCCCCUGGAGAGGCACGCACUGGAGUGAGGGAGCGCCCUAAGGCUUUGGUUGGACAUGCAUGCUUCCUGACCCUCCGAUGUGAGAAUGUGGGGUGUGGAGACAAGAGUGACUCCAUCUUGGAUGCUGAUAUAGUUUGGCUCUGUGUCCCCAUCCAAAUCUCACCUUUAAUUGUAAUCCCUAUAAUCCCCACGUGUUAAGGGCAGGACCAGGUGGAGGUAAUUGAAUCUUGGGGGCAGUUUCUCCCAUGCUGUUCUCGUGAUAAUGAGUGAGUCUCAUGAGAUCUGAUGGUUUUGUAAGUGUCUGGCAUUUCCCCUGCUUGUACUCAUUCUCUCUCCUACUGCCCCGUGAAGAGGUGCCUUCCGCCAUGAUUGUCUGUUUCUUGAGGCCUCUCCAGCCAUCUGGAACCGUGAGUCAAUUAAACCUCUUUUCUUUAUAAAUUAUCCGGCCUCAGGUAUUUCUUCAUAGCAAUGUGAGAAUGAACUAAUACAGAUGCUAAUCUGCCCUGUUGACUUCUGAUUAGCCCUGGUCCUGUGAAAACCUCCUGAUUCUCACUUUAUUUACUGUCUUUAGCGUAAGAACAUGUCAGCCUUGAUGUUAUUGCACAAAUUAUAGGUUAUGAUGCAUGUAGCAUUCUUGCCUGUUCUGGAGGGCUGCCUUUAAUUGUCUUGCAUAGAGCAUGUAUACCCUUUCCCUGUGAUAUAUAAGCCCUGGGUCUGGGGAGCAACAGUGUGGAGAUCUACCUGUUUUGCUGCUCUCCAAGACUACACUUCCAUCCUUAAGUUCCCCAAAUAAAUCACUCUGUACUGACAAA